AGGCAGCAGGCUGGAGCUCAGCCCAGCAGUGGAAUCCAGGAGCCCAGAGGUGGCCGGGUGCUGACGUGAUGGCCACAGCAGGAAAUCCCUGGGGCUGGUUCCUGGGGUACCUCAUCCUUGGUGUCGCAGGAUCGCUCGUCUCUGGUAGCUGCAGCCAAAUCAUAAACGGCGAGGACUGCAGCCCGCACUCGCAGCCCUGGCAGGCGGCACUGGUCAUGGAAAACGAAUUGUUCUGCUCGGGCGUCCUGGUGCAUCCGCAGUGGGUGCUGUCAGCCGCACACUGUUUCCAGAACUCCUACACCAUCGGGCUGGGCCUGCACAGUCUUGAGGCCGACCAAGAGCCAGGGAGCCAGAUGGUGGAGGCCAGCCUCUCCGUACGGCACCCAGAGUACAACAGACCCUUGCUCGCUAACGACCUCAUGCUCAUCAAGUUGGACGAAUCCGUGUCCGAGUCUGACACCAUCCGGAGCAUCAGCAUUGCUUCGCAGUGCCCUACCGCGGGGAACUCUUGCCUCGUUUCUGGCUGGGGUCUGCUGGCGAACGGCAGAAUGCCUACCGUGCUGCAGUGCGUGAACGUGUCGGUGGUGUCUGAGGAGGUCUGCAGUAAGCUCUAUGACCCGCUGUACCACCCCAGCAUGUUCUGCGCCGGCGGAGGGCAAGACCAGAAGGACUCCUGCAACGGUGACUCUGGGGGGCCCCUGAUCUGCAACGGGUACUUGCAGGGCCUUGUGUCUUUCGGAAAAGCCCCGUGUGGCCAAGUUGGCGUGCCAGGUGUCUACACCAACCUCUGCAAAUUCACUGAGUGGAUAGAGAAAACCGUCCAGGCCAGUUAACUCUGGGGACUGGGAACCCAUGAAAUUGACCCCCAAAUACAUCCUGCGGAAGGAAUUCAGGAAUAUCUGUUCCCAGCCCCUCCUCCCUCAGGCCCAGGAGUCCAGGCCCCCAGCCCCUCCUCCCUCAAACCAAGGGUACAGAUCCCCAGCCCCUCCUCCCUCAGACCCAGGAGUCCAGACCCCCCAGCCCCUCCUCCCUCAGACCCAGGAGUCCAGCCCCUCCUCCCUCAGACCCAGGAGUCCAGACCCCCCAGCCCCUCCUCCCUCAGACCCAGGAGUCCAGCCCCUCCUCCCUCAGACCCAGGAGUCCAGACCCCCCAGCCCCUCCUCCCUCAGACCCAGGGGUCCAGGCCCCCAACCCCUCCUCCCUCAGACUCAGAGGUCCAGGCCCCCAACCCCUCCUUCCCCAGACCCAGAGGUCCAGGUCCCAGCCCCUCCUCCCUCAGACCCAGCGGUCCAAUGCCACCUAGACUCUCCCUGUACACAGUGCCCCCUUGUGGCACGUUGACCCAACCUUACCAGUUGGUUUUUCAUUUUUUGUCCCUUUCCCCUAGAUCCAGAAAUAAAGUCUAAGAGAAGCGCA